AUGAAAGACUCGGCUUCUGCUGCUAGCGCCGGAGCUGAGUUAGUUCUGAGAAGGUUUCCCUGGGCGUUCCUUGUCCGGCGGCCUCUGCUGCCGCCUCCGGAGACGCUUCCCGAUAGAUGGCUACAGGCCGCGGAGGAGGAGGAGGUGGAGUUGCUGCCCUUCCGGAGUCCGCCCCGUGAGGAGAAUGUCCCAGAAAUCCUGGAUAGAAAGCACUUUGACCAAGAGGGAAUGUGUAUAUAUUAUACCAAGUUCCAAGGACCCUCACAGAUGCCUUCCAGGAUGUCAAAUUUGUCAGCAACUCGUCAGGUGUUUUUGUGGUCGCUUGGUCAAGCAACAUGCUUGUUUUACUGCAAGUCUUGCCAUGAAAUACUCAGAUGUGAAAUUGGGUGA